CCCCGGUACUCCUUCCUGGACCGCGCUGGAAGCCCUGGCGGCGGCGGCCCAUGGGGCCCUUGGCGCUGCCCGCCUGGCUGCAGCCCAGGUAGGGCGCUCGGCCGAAUCCCGAGGGGAGGGGGCGCGGGUGGAGGGCCUGGAGGCGGGAGCUCCCCUCUGCGGCGGGCGGGCGGGCGGCACCCCCCGCCCGCCAGCAAGGCGCAGCGCUACCGUGCCCAGGCACCCCUUGGAGCUCAUGCAGGUAUAGGAAGAAUGCGUAUCUUUUCAUCUAUUACUUAAUCCAGUUCUGUGGCCACUCUUGGAUAUUUACAAAUAUGACAGUCAGAUUCUUUUCAUUUGGAAAAGAUUCAAUGGUUGACACUUUUUAUGCUAUUGGACUUGUGAUGCGACUUUGCCAAUCCGUAUCUCUCCUGGAACUGCUGCACAUAUAUGUUGGCAUUGAGUCAAACCAUCUUCUCCCAAGGUUUUUGCAGCUCACAGAAAGAAUAAUCAUCCUUUUUGUGGUGAUCACCAGUCAAGAGGAAGUCCAAGAGAAAUAUGUGGUGUGUGUUUUAUUCGUCUUUUGGAAUCUAUUGGAUAUGGUUAGGUACACUUAUAGCAUGUUAUCAGUCAUAGGAAUAUCCUAUGCUGUCUUGACAUGGCUCAGUCAAACACUAUGGAUGCCAAUUUAUCCUUUGUGUGUUCUUGCUGAAGAGGCAAAGUUGAAGAGGGAAGCAGCUCUGCACAGUAGACAAAAUACUGGACAAAAAGCAACGGCAUCUGAGGCCUUCACUUCAUUAACUCACUGUAUGAAACCAUCUAGUUGCAGGAAAAUAAGCUCAGGGCUCCCACUGAUUCUGCAUUAUGCAUUUGCCAUCUAUCAAUCGCUGCCUUAUUUUGAAUCAUUUGGCACUUAUUCCACCAAGCUGCCCUUUGACUUAUCCAUCUAUUUCCCAUAUGUGCUGAAAAUAUAUCUCAUGAUGCUCUUUAUAGGUAUGUAUUUUACCUACAGUCAUCUAUACUCAGAAAGAAGAGACAUCCUCGGAAUCUUUCCCAUUAAAAAAAAGAAGAUGUGAAGUACAGCAUUCCAGUGUGACACGAGAAAAGACAGGCUGUGGAUUCAGUGCAGUAAAUAAAACACAGGAAGUAUUCUGGUGGAAAAAUACCUUGUAUUUGAUAAAAAUCCAUUACAUGAAAUAACUGCACAUACCCCCAAAACUCUAGACAUAACAGGCUAUGUUUUUCACACAUUGUAUUUUUAAGACAUAUAUAUUCUCCAUACCCUGCUUCACCAAAAUUCCUGCUUCAUUUGGAUUUUAUACAAGUUAUACUUACAUUGUAUGAAGUCUGAUUAUUUUCCUGUAAGUUUAAUGAGAAAUAGGAGAUUAGCUGCAAUAGAUUCAAUUAAAUUAAGAAACCAAACUUGAUAACCUAAAUUACAUGUAUUCUUUUUCACUUCCAAGUUCCCAAAUAGAUCUGUAGGAGAAGAGGGAUGGAAAAUAUAUUCCACAGUUGCCUAGAAUAACAUAUUUCAUAGACAGAUGUCUGUCUUCAGAUCUAAUAAUACUCACCCUAAACAUUAGAUAUGUUUAGAAAAUUAAAUAUCUUUCCAAGCCCUAUGUCUUAGCUCAGGUUGCUAUAAUAGAACACCAUAAACCGAAUGGCUUAAACAACAGCAAACGCUUCUCACAGUUCUGGAGGCUGGGAAUUCCGCUCAGGAUCAAGGCAUCAGCUAAUGCAGUUUCUGGUGAGGGCCCUCUUCCCAGUUUGCAGAUAGAUGUCCUUCUUUGUCCUCACAUGAGAGAGAGAUCAACUCUCUUAUGUCUCUUAUAAUGGCACUAACCCCAUUCAUGAGGGCUCUACCCUCAUGAUCUAAUUACCUCCCAAUGGCCCCACCUCCAAAUACCAUCAUAUUGGAGGUUAGGGCUUAACACAUGAAUUUUGGGGGAACACAAAGAUUCACUCCAUAGCAUUCUGUACCUGGUCCUACAAAAUUCAUGUCCUCCUCACAUGCAAAAUACAUACAUUCCAUCUCGACAGCCUCAAAAGUCUUAACUCAUUCCUGCAUCAACUCUAAAGUCCAAAGUCUCGUCUAAAUCAGAUGUGGGUGAGAUUCAAGGUAGAAUUCAUCCUGAGGUAAAAUUCCUUUCCAGCUUUGAACUUGUGAAAUGAAACAAGUUAUGUGCUUCCACAGUACAAUGGUGGGACACACAAAGGGUGGACAUUCCUAUUCCCAAAGCAAGAAACAGGAAAAAAGGAAGGUGUAAUGGGUCCCCAGCAAGUCCAAAACCUAGCAAGGCAAACACCAUGAGAUCUUCAGUCUUAGUAAUAAUCCUCUUUGGCCUGAUACUCUGGCUUCAGGACCCAGUGAGGCAGAGGUAUUGCCCCCAGGACUAUGUUGGAGGAGGAUGACCCCCAUAUCACCAGGCGGAAGCUGUCAGGCCUGUUGAAACCAAGGCAAUGACUGCCCCUUUUGAAACUGAGAAGGUACCACUGAUGUUCUCUGAAUCAUUGUUCCGGGUCAGUUUCUCCUUUUCUUGAAGAAUAGUGUACAUUCACAGCUGAAUAGCUCUAUGGUCCCAAAUUCAAGAAGUCCAACAGUCUUCCCUCAUUCUGUCCCAUCUCCAUUCCUUUCAAUACAAACUAGCAGUGUUCCUGCUGGGGUGGCUGAUUAGGUCUGUGGUUCACACCCACAUAAAUCUAAUUGGAUGACUUGUCUGCUACACUCUUAGUGUUCUCUACCAAACGUGUUUUCUUAUCUUUUUGUAAUGCAGACAGACUGAUAAUUUCCCACAUCUUUUAAGUUCUGGUUCCGUUUUUGUUAAGAAUUCUGUCUUCAUUUUUUGUCACAUUUUACUUUAAGCAGUCAAGAUAAACCGAGGCACUCCUUCAACACUGGUUGGAGAUCUCUUCAGUUCAAUAUCUAAUUUCAUGGCUCACAAUUUUACUUUCCACAAAACACUAGAACAUGAACACAAUCAUCCAAGUUCUUUGGCAUAUUAUAACAAAGAUCACCUUUCUUCCAGUUUCCCAUAACAGGUUCCUCAUUUUCAUUUGAGACUUCAUCAGAAUGGCCUUUAUUGUCCAUGUCUACCAACAUUAUCUUCAUGGUGAUUUACGUGUUCUCUAUGAAGAUGGAGGCUUUCUCUCCCACCCUCUUCUCUUUGAGCCCUCACCAAAAUCACCUCUAUCAAUCCCUUCAUGGCAAUACUGGCUUUUUCUAGCAAAAAAACUAGUACCUCAAAACUCUUCCAGUACUCUUCCAGGUACUCUAGUACCUCAAAACUCUUCCAGCUUCUAUCUGUUACCUAACGUCAAAGCUGCUUCCACAUCUUUAUAUAUUGGUUAUAGCAUCACCACACUUCUUGGUACUAAUUGCUGUCUUAGCUUGGCUGCUAUAACAAAAUACCAUAAACUGGGUGGCUUAGACAACAAAUAUAUUUCUCACAGUUCUGGAGGCAGGGAAGUCCAAGAUAAAGGUGCUAGACAAUUAAGUUCCUGAUGAGGUUCCAAGGUGCUAGCUGAUUCUUCUUCAUGGUUUGCAGAUGAAUGCCUUCUUGCUAUAUGUUCACAUGGUGGAGGGAGAAACCAUCUCUCCCUUAUUUCUUAUUGUAAAGGUACUAAUCCCAUUUAUGAAGGUUCCAGCUUCAAAUGCCAUCACACUGGAGAUUAGAUUUUCAACAUGUGAAUUUAAUGGGGGACACCAGCAUUCAGUCCCUAGUGCUCUGAUAGAGUAUUCAUUAAUGUCAUGUAUUUGUUAACAUCUUGUAAGUUAUUUGGGCUUUGAUGCCUUAAAAGAAGACCCUGGCCAGGCAUGCUGGCUCAUACCUGUAAUCCUAGCACUAUGAGAGGCUGAGGUGGGCAGAUCAGUUGAGGUCAGGAGUUCAAGACCAGCCUGGCCAACAUGGUGAAACCCCAUUUCUACUAAAAAUACAAAAAUUAGCCAGGCAUGGUGGCGCAUGCCUGUAAUCCCAGCUACACGGGAGGCUGGGGGCAUGAGAAUCGCUUGAGCCCAGGAGAUGGAGGUUGCAGUGAGCAGAGAUUGAGCCACUGCACUCCAGCCUGGGUGACAGAGUGAGACUCUAUCUCAAAAGAGAAGACCCUAAUGAAAAUAGUAAACCUUUAGCAAAUACACAAAUGAUGCCCCAUUCUGUAUUCUUUUUAAUUUUAAAAAUAAUGACACACACAUACAGGAAGAUAAAAGGUAUAAAAAUAUACUAAGUACUUUUUAAAAAGGAAAAUUCAUGUUUUGGAUUAUUACUGAAUUGUUGCUAAUUACUGUAAUGUAAGUCAUAUGUCCUUACAUAGUUUUGAAAAAUGCUUUCUUUGAAAAUCUAAAAAAAGUGUGAAUAACUGAUAGUCAUUGCUGUAUCAUUGAUGUAUCACUCAAUUUUUGGUAAAGAAUUAUAAAGAUCUUACCUAGAAACUAUGUAAAAAGGUAUUAAAUAUAUUGUGAUGUAAGAAUAGGAUAAUAAAAAUGUAAUUUUAAAAAUGGGUAACUUAUUUCCACUAAAGAAAACAUUUGGAAAGAAACAAUUGAGUAUUAGGCUACUUGAAAUCUUUAUAAAUAUAUUUGGAUUUUAAAAAAUUAUCCUUUUAAAAAGCUACAUUUUUUCUGCUUUUAUAGUUAUCUUCUAAAUUUCAGAAAAAUUAUGAAAAGCUUUAGUGUGCAAGGAGAACAUAAACCCUUUGCAAAUUUUAGGUGAGUUAAUCUUAAUCACUCCAAAUAAAGAUGGCUCCUUACACUGCCGAAGUACAUGUACAAUCAAUCACUAAAACAAAGAGAAAAUUAGAGAAACUACACUUUACUGGGUCAUUAUAAUAAAUUAAAAUUUCAUUAUUAAAUAAUGCUUUAAUUUUUUAAAACCAGAUUAACUUAAAAACUUCUUAAAAUUGAAAACCAAAAGAAACACAAGUGAAUUUAUAAUUAUUUUAAAACAGAAAUGAGGAUUGACAGUAAUUUGAGAUAUCUGCAACAAUUGUAACAUAAAAAGAUCUUACAUUUCCUUUGGUGACAGACACAAUUGUUAAUACUACUGUGGUUGGUUGCCUGUAUUCACAAUGGAAAGGAAUACUAAAUUUCAUUAUCAAUUAGUGAAAAUAAAGGUGUAAUUUCUUUUUCUACUUAAGUACAUGUUCCCCAGGUUAAGAAACCCAGACAUAGUGAAGUCAAGACAGUAACUAUCUGGUUAAUCGGAUGUUACCAAAAUCGCAAAGUUGAUGUCUUUGACUAUCUGUCUUAACUGUAUGUUCACCAAAUCCCUAUUUCAUUUUGUACAGUGUAGACAAAGGCUUACUUUCUCAAAUCUAAGUAACAUAGAUGAAAUAGGAACCAUUAGAUAUUUUGAAAACAUAUCUAAGACAACUUUUUUCAGUAAUUUUUUUAUUGUGGUAAAAUGUAAAAUAUACUAUCUUAUUCCUUUUUAAGUGUGCAGUUCAGUAGUAGUAAGUAAUUUAUAUUGUGCAACCAUCACCACUGUCCAUCUCCAGAACUUUUUUUACCUUGCAAAACUUAUACCCUAUACUCAUUAAGCAAUGGUUCCCUAUUCUCCCAUCUGCCCUGUCCCUGGCAACCACCAGUCUACUUUUUGUCUCUAUGAUUUUGAUUGCUCUAAGUACCUCAUAUAAAUGUAAUCAUACAGUAUCUGUCUUUCGUAAUUGGCUUAUUUCACUUAGCAUAAUGUCUGCAAGUUUCCUCCAUUUUGUAUAUGUCAGAAUUUUCUUCCUUUUUGAGGAUGACUGAUAAGGAGGGACUUACUCCUGUCAUUUUGCUAUUUGUUUUCUACAUAGCUUAGCUUUUUUGUCCCUCAUUUCCUGCAUUACGUCUUUUGUGUGUAGUUUACUUUUUUAUAGUGAAGCAUUUAAGUAUCUUUCUCAGUUCUUUUGUGUAUAUUCUGUAGCUGUUUUCUUUGUGGUUACCAUAGGGUGACAUUUAAUAUCCGGAAGGUAAUUUGGACUUAUGCCAGCUGAACUUCAAAAAUAUACAAAAAUUCUGCUCUUUAUAUCUCUGUCUAUCACUCCUUUAAGUUUCACAAAAUUAUAUACACUGUGUGUCCAAAAUCAAUUUUUAAAAAUGCAGUAGUCUCUAUGUAGAAAACAAAAAGUGGAGUUACAAACCAUUGUUACAAAAGUACUAGAUUUUAUAAUUGCCCAUGUAUUUUUCUUUACUGAGAUCCUUAUUUCUUCAUGUGGCUUUGAGUUGCUGUUUAGUGUCUUUCCAUUUCAACUUGCAGGACCCCUAUUAGCAUUUCUGGCAGGGGCAGGUCUAGUGGUAACAUACUUUCUCAGCUUUUGUUUAUCUGGGGAUGUCUUAAUUUCUCUCUCACGUUUGAAGAACAGUUUUGUCAAAUACAGGAAAUGUGGUUGAUGAUAUAUUUUUUUCCUAACACUUUGAAUAUGUGAGCUCACUGCAUUCUGGCCUCCAAAGUUUCUGAUGAGAAAUCUGAUAAUCUUAUUAAGGAUCACUUAUAUGUGAUGAAUUGAUUUUUUCAUGCUACUUUCAAGAUUCUCUUUCUGUCUUUGGCUUUUGAUAGUUGUGUGGAUCUCUUGGAAUUCAUUCUACUUGGAGUUUGUUGGUCAUUAUCUGGCUGUUCUUCAAAUAUUCUCUCUGCUCCUUUCUUUCUCUCUUUUCCUUCUGGGAUCCUCACAAUGUGUAUGUUGGUCUGCUUGAUGGGUCCCACAGAUCCUUAUACCCUGUUCACUUUUUUCCAAUUUUUUUCUAUUGCUCAGACUAAUAAUUUCCAUUGUCCUAUUUUCAUGUAUACUGAUUCUUCUGCUGCCCAAAUCUGCCUUUGAAUACCUCUAGUGAGUUUUUCAUUUCAAUUAUCGUACUUUCCAGCUCUUGAAUUUCUUUUUUGUAUCGUCUUAGAUUUUCUCUAUAUUGAUAUUACCAUUUUGUUCAUCCAUUGGUUUUUUGACUUUUUCCGCAUGCUCUUUGGUUCUUUAAAAAACAUCCUUAAGGCAGUCGUUGUAGAGCCUUUAGUGGAUCCACCAUCAAGUCUUUUUCAGAGAUAGUUUUUGUUUUUGUUUUCAUUUGAAAGGGACAUACUUUCCUGUUUCUUUGUAUGCCUUGUUAUUUUUUUGCUGAAAACUGAACGUUUCAAUCUAAUAAUAUGGUAACUACAUCUCACUAAGGUCCCUAAGUUAAUGUUUUUUUUUAAACUAUUCCUUACUUUGCCUGCCUUGAGCAAGUUGUCAAAUGUGAGAAACUGUAUUUAUUUCAGAAGUACAAAUAGAUACAAUCUCAAUGUCCAAAAUAUUUCCCCAAAGAAAGAAUCUUACAAUUAUUUAAGUUUACUUAUGGAGAAAACAUUUUAUGGUACUAAAGUGUUAAAGUGAUUUAAAAUUAAGGUUAAAAUAUGCUAAAAAUUAUCUUCCUUUACCCAGUAUCUAUCUUCCACUUGUUUAUUACUGCUUUUUAAUAAUUAUAAUGUUUCCCGUUGGUUCGGAUAAUUUUAAUAUUCUUCUCGGUCUGAGUUAUAUGCUAAUGUUGAUAUGACAUGGUUCUCCAGGGUAGUGUUCAGAUUGUAUGUUCAGGGAGCAACAGCCACAAUUAACAAGUUCACCUGUUUAGAAUGCAGAUUCCAGGGCUCCACUAAAGAUAGUUGAAUCAGAAGCUCUGGGAAUAAGCUCAGGAUCCUACCUUUUGAUAGACUCCUCAAAUGAGCCUCAUGCACAGAAAAGUUUGAGAACCACUGCUUUUGAGUCUAAAUUAUUUCAGCUUUGGACAGAAAGAAAACUGCUAAAAAGAACUACUUAUAUAAAAGCCACCAAUGUUUUCAGAACAGGGAUGAUUUUUUAUGGCUUUAAAAAUCCUUAAAUAGUAGUUCUGAACAUGUUUUUAACAUGCCAAGUAAGAAUUACUAACUAGUUUAUUUUUGCUAAGGGUAGCUGGAGUUUUAAAUCUCAUCUAAAAUAAGGUUAGUUAAUUCCAUAUGAAAGUCAAUUAGUAAAAGUAUGCCUUAAUUCAUCACAUACAUGUAGGUGUCUAUUGUUACUUCAUGGUAUUCAGCUGAAUGAUGGGGUUCUUGUGAAAGAUAAUGUGGUCUGGAAUUAAGAGCACUAGGUUUGAUUUGAGAUCAAGCUCCAUUAUUUACUAACUGAAUGACUCUUUGAGUUCCAGUUUCCUUAACCACUUAAAGUUAUUAUGAAGACUAAAUGACAUAUGGUAAAUUAAACUUUUGCAAAUUAUAAAGGGCUUUGCAGAAGUAGGACAUUUAUAACAUGUUCUGUUCUUACUUCAUGAUGGUUUAGUGAUUUAUAUUCUCUGACUGUAAGUUCCAUGAGAGCAGGGAUGACACGUUUUGUUCAGAUUGUACCCCAGAAACUUGUAUAGUGGCACAUAAUAGACACCCAUAAUUGUGUGUGCAACUCUAUCUUUAAAGAACGCCACUACUACAUCUAGAAAUAUAUUUCAAGAAAUCUAUCGGCUUAAUUAGGUAAUGAAUUUCAAUUGUAUCUCAAAGCGUUCCUUAUAUUUAGAAGACACAUAAGUUUUGUUUUUUUCUUUCAACUUAUAUAAGUAUCUUAACAUGCUACUUCUAGAAUAUUUUAAUUGUUAAGAACAAUUUCUUAAUAAACUUCCACUGUCUUCCUGAGUCCCCA